ACGGCGCGGUGACGCAGCGCGACGGCGGCGGCGGCGGCGGCGGCGGUGGUCGGUGCGGGAGGAGGGAGGGGAGCUUGCGGGCCCGAGAGGGGGCGACGGCGGCGGCGGUGGCCUGAGGAGGCCCGAGCGGCGGCGGUGGCGGCGAAGGCCGAGGCGUCUAGGUGUUUUUGGAAGAGCUGCAGCCUUUGAAGAAACAUCUCUUGAUGAUGAUAUCAUAGACUCCUUCCUACUGGGCAGAUGAGGCAGAAUGGGGCACAGUAGUUCCAGCAAAAAUCCAGAGAGGACUAUCCUUGGCCAGGCUUUACCCCAUGUCCACUUCUGGAGCCAAGAAAGACAGUUCCUUCUCCAAGGGGAACCCAGGGUGUUGAUACUAGAAGAUGGAAAUGGAUACAGUAAGAUGCUGCCACAGUGAGAUGCCUCACCCAGGUCUCCCUCUGUCACUUCAGCCAAGCACAUGGGAUAGAAAGUAGCAGGCGGCCUCUGGCCCUUUAAUGGAAGAGGGCCAUCCAGUCCUCUCCAGUUAACAUCUAGACCGAACACAAAGCAUCCUUCUCUCAUCCAGAAGACAUAGGAACCCUACCUUCAGGGAUGAUUUUUUUUUAACAGUGAAAUCUUAAAAGUAACUGUUUCACUAAAGCCUCCAGUAUUUACUGAAGACUGUCAGAAUCAUCCUCCAUCACUAGAUCUUCUCCACCAGUCAUGUUCCCUGAGCAGUGGGGUGGCUUGAAGGUAUAAACCAGAGAGGCCCAAGGGAGGGAUAGUUAGCAGACUUCUGGUCUUUUUCUAGUUUGUGCUCUUCUGUUCCAAGGACCACAGGAUUCUUCUCAUCGCAGUGCUCCAGGCAGCCACUACCAAUCGAUUGGAGUUAGCCUGUGAGGAAACUGGAGAGGCGUGGCUGGACCAAGACCUCCCCCCAUGUGAGCAGGCUUCCUCCUCCCCCAACAACCGUUGCCACCACGCCCAGAAACGUCCUUAAGCCCUGGCCCUCAGGGGAAAGGUAACAGGAGGCCAGAGCCGGGACCAUGUGACGGCGCUGGCCCUCGCCACCGCCGUCCCCCGACCCUGGCCCCAGGCCCGGCACCAUGAUGUUCCGAGACCAGGUGGGCAUCCUCGCUGGCUGGUUCAAAGGCUGGAAUGAGUGUGAGCAGACAGUGGCCCUCCUGUCACUUCUGAAACGGGUCACCCGUACCCAGGCCCGCUUCCUGCAGCUCUGCCUGGAGCACUCACUGGCGGACUGCAAUGACAUCCACCUGCUGGAGUCGGAGGCCAACAGUGCUGGUGAGUCCACCCUUAGAGAUGGGAGCCAGCAGGAG